AUGCGAGGCUCCCGCUCUCCACCACAAGCAACGAAGCCUGCAAGCUGUUCGAUGCCACGCUGACCCAGGACUCUGAGUGGUGGGUGGACAGCGGUGGGUGCAGUGGGGAUGUUUUUUGAGGAUGCUGGCCUCCCCGGGCCUCCCAUUGUGGCCUGCUGAGGGUCUGAUGCAGGGCUCGGCUGCUUAGGACGUGGGAUCCUGUCCUGGGAUGAAUCUUAUGUAAAAUGGACCAAUGACAAGAGUCUCGGUGGCAUCGAGGGCUGCCUGUCAAAGCUCAAAGCAGCAGAUCCAACCUUUGUGAUGGGCCACGCCAUGGCUACUGGCCUUGUGCUGAUUGGCACUGGAAGCUCCGUGAAGCUGGACAAAGAGCUGGACCUGGCUGUGAAGACAAUGGUGGAGAUUUCAAGAACCCAGCCGCUGACAAGGCGGGAGCAGCUGCACGUGUCUGCAGUAGAGACAUUUGCCAAUGGGAACUUUCCGAAAGCCUGUGAACUAUGGGAACAGAUUCUCCAGGACCACCCGACAGACAUGUUGGCCCUGAAAUUUUCCCAUGAUGCUUAUUUUUACCUGGGCUAUCAGGAACAGAUGAGAGAUUCUGUUGCUCGAAUUUACCCCUUCUGGACACCUGACAUCCCCCUAAGCAGCUAUGUGAAAGGCAUCUACUCUUUUGGCUUGAUGGAAACCAACUUCUACGACCAGGCAGAAAAACUCGCCAAAGAGGCUUUAUCUAUUAACCCGACAGACGCAUGGUCGGUGCACACCGUCGCUCACAUCCACGAGAUGAAAGCAGAGAUCAAGGAUGGGUUGGAAUUCAUGCAGCACUCAGAGACCUUCUGGAAGGACUCUGAUAUGUUGGCUUGUCAUAACUAUUGGCACUGGGCUUUAUAUCUGAUUGAGAAGGGCGAAUAUGAGGCCGCGCUGACCAUCUACGAUACCCACAUCCUUCCCAGCCUGCAGGCCAACGAUGCAAUGCUGGACGUGGUGGACAGCUGCUCCAUGCUCUACCGCCUGCAGAUGGAAGGAGUGUCUGUGGGCCAGCGGUGGCAGGAUGUCCUGCCUGUGGCCCGGAAGCACAGCCGAGACCACAUCCUGCUGUUCAAUGACGCACACUUCCUGAUGGCAUCCCUGGGUGCACACGACCCCCAGACCACACAGGAGCUGCUGACCACCCUGCGGGACGCCAGCGAAUCCCCAGGGGAGAACUGCCAGCACCUCCUGGCCCGAGACGUGGGGCUGCCCCUGUGCCAGGCCCUGGUGGAGGCUGAGGACGGGAACCCUGACCGCGUCCUGGAGCUGCUCCUGCCCAUCCGCUACCGGAUCGUCCAGCUCGGUGGGAGCAAUGCCCAGAGAGACGUCUUCAACCAGCUGCUGAUUCACGCGGCCUUAAACUGCACCUCCAGCGUCCAUAAGAACGUAGCCCGGAGCCUUCUGAUGGAGCGUGAUGCCUUGAAGCCCAACUCGCCCCUGACCGAGCGGCUCAUCCGCAAGGCAGCUACCGUCCACCUCAUGCAGUGAGCCAGCCUGGCCGCCUCCACCCUGCAGAACCUCAGUGGUGGCGUCACUGCGUCCAGUCAGCUGCUCCACCGGGUUAGGGUCAGGAGACGGCCAGAGCCUGUUUGUUAGGGCUGUUAGAGGGUGAUCUUCAGUUUUACAGGAAGUGGGUCACGGGUUAAUUUUAAAUGUGAUUCCGAAUCUCCUUUCAGUCCUCGAGAAGGGCCAAUGAGCAUUUUUCAGCAGUCACAGCCAGUGUGAGUGCUGCUCUUUCCACCUGCCUUGCAAAUUCUGUUUCCCAGGGGAAUGUGUCUACUGCCUGGUGGUUCAAAGGUUGGAAGGCAGGGCAGAGGUGGGGGCUGAUUCUGCUGGGACAGGUCUUCCAGAGGCAGCCUCCCCCCACUGCCUGUCCCCGUCCCCACCAGGCUGCCCUUGGGAUGGACCUUUUCAUUCUUUUCUUUAUAUUCUAGACAGUCUCUGUUGUCUCAUUGUGUUGCUGUCCCAUUUUUCAGGUGAGGGUACCGGGGUAGGGGAGUGGCCUGCCCAGGGUCACACUAUGAGAGGCCCCCACCUGCUGCCUUUGGACGCAGCCCCCUGCUGCUGCAUCCACCACCCUUCUUACAGAUCAGCGCGCACAUGGGGUCCUUCUGCUGUCUCUGGGGCGAGUCUUGGAGCCCCCUGGGGGGCUCUGUUGGUGCUGAUUUGGACCCGUUUCUCUUUUUAAACUGCACAUCAUAACAGGGCUUCAUGUCGAGCAUGAUUUUAAUCAUAAAUGCACUUCUGAGGUGCAAGGAUUGAGCUCAGAGCUGCUCUGUUGUGGCAAAACCCAAAGUGCUGUGAUGUGUGGCUGUGACAAGCCUGGAGCGGGUCCUGUGAGCGCCGCCUCUGUCUCCUGCUUCCCCACUGAACGCCUGCUGAAUGUGCCGCUGACUCAGCUGUGCUGCUUUCAGCCCUCCUGUGAGGGGCGGUCCCAGUGCACAGAUGUUUUUCAAGUUCCUCAGUUUGUACUGAAAUUAGGGAUUCAUCAGGGCAGGAAGCAGGCAGGCCUCUCAGAAGGGAGAGGAGGCCUCCAAAUCUAUUGAGUCCCCACAGUUUGCUCAAGCCCAGGCAAAUUUCUGUGAUUAAAAUGAAUUCAUCAGUUCCUCCAA